GCAGCUGCCAUCUUAGGGGCGCCUGGCGCUACGGGUUUCUCGUUGGAGGCGGCCUUCGUGGCAGCUGUAGACGCCGGGAAAAGGCAUAAAGUCCGUUGGCCGACACCUUUCUUUCCUCCGGCCUCGGUAGAACCGCCAGCCCGCGUCCGAAGGCGGAGGCGAGGGGAACUGGCCGCGUGAGGGGCCUGAGGCGAGCGGUUAGAGCGUCUCCCGGAAGGAUGGGCCGGUCUCGGAGCCGGAGCUCGUCCCGCUCCAAGCACACCAAGAGCAGCAAGCACAACAAGAAGCGCAGCCGGUCCCGGUCGCGAUCCCGGGACAAGGAGCGCGUGCGGAAGCGUUCCAAAUCUCGGGAAAGUAAACGGAACCGGCGGCGGGAGUCGCGGUCCCGUUCGCGCUCCACCAACACGGCCGUGUCCCGGCGCGAGCGGGACCGGGAGCGCGCCUCGUCCCCGCCCGACCGCAUCGACAUCUUCGGGCGCACGGUGAGCAAGCGCAGCAGCCUGGACGAGAAGCAGAAGCGAGAGGAGGAGGAGAAGAAAGCGGAGUUCGAGCGGCAGCGAAAAAUUCGACAGCAAGAAAUAGAAGAAAAACUCAUCGAGGAAGAAACAGCACGAAGAGUAGAAGAAUUGGUAGCAAAAAGGGUGGAGGAAGAACUGGAGAAAAGGAAGGAUGAAAUUGAACGAGAAGUUCUCCGAAGGGUGGAGGAAGCCAAACGCAUCAUGGAAAAGCAGUUGCUCGAAGAACUCGAGCGACAGAGACAAGCUGAGCUUGCCGCACAAAAAGCUAGAGAGGAGGAAGAACGUGCAAAACGUGAGGAGCUAGAGCGAAUACUGGAAGAGAAUAACCGAAAAAUUGCAGAAGCACAAGCCAAACUGGCCGAAGAACAGUUGAGAAUUGUUGAAGAACAAAGAAAGAUUCAUGAGGAAAGGAUGAAACUAGAACAAGAACGACAACGUCAACAAAAAGAAGAACAAAAAAUUAUCCUGGGCAAGGGGAAGUCCAGGCCAAAACUGUCCUUCUCAUUAAAAACCCAGGAUUAAAUUGCAAACUCUGAACUUUUUACAAAGAAAAAUGGAAAAACUUUGUAUGGUAGCUUCAUGUUGAAGUGGUUUUUUGUUUUUGUUUUUGUUUUUUUAAUUUGUAAAAUCUGGAAAGUUAGCUUGUUCUAAUAGGGGCUAUGCUCUGCAAUUCCCUUUUUUUUUUUUUUUUUCCUUCCACUAAGUCAAAUCCUUAUCAGAUCAUUGUUGUAUUCUAAGGAGUGACGUAUUUUUCACCUGUUUGGAUUCUAUAUUAGUGGUCUGAGGAAGAGCAGAUCACAUUGUAAAACUAUGGAUGGUCUGAUAAGGCUUUUACUGACCCCACUGACUUCAGAGUUAUACUCUGUUUGCUACAUCAUAAUGCUGGUUUUGCUGACUUUUUGUUUUUUUAUAUAUUUAUAAAAAAAGAAAAAGUUGGUGAUUGCAUUGGGAAAUUCCCAGGGUAUUACUGGACCUAUGUGGUGUAUUGUUAAACCAGUGUCCUUGUGAUACUGUUGCUCUUGAUGUUCCUGAUACAGGUAAGGAAACAGUUGGUCAACUCUGAUACAAAGUAUAUAUACAGUUCAGUAUUGUCUCUGUUCAUUUUGUUUUUAUUUCAUUGACAAAAUCAAACCAGCAUUCCCCAUUGUGUAAAUAAAUGAUUUUGCUGAAUAAAGUAAAGUCUUAAAUUCAUAUGUUGAAGCAAUUUUUUUUAAUGUUAUGUUAAGUCUUAAAGAGGGUGGUUCACUUUUUGAUGGUCAACCAUUUAGAAGUCUUAGAACUAUAUUUCCUCUUGUUUAUACUUUUAACAUAGGGUUUAUAUGUACAUUAAAUAUACUUGUGAAUUAGUAUUUAAUGGCUAUUUUUACAAAUAUCAACUUUAUGCUGAUAGAGCAAAUGGCAUCAGUGUUACCUUUAAGAAAGACUAACAACAUCCAGAAGAUUUAAAUUCUCAAACCUGUGCCUCUGUUUUAGGAUAUAAGUAUUAUCACAAAGUAUACUUAAUAAAGGCUAGAAAAAUGCUUUUAAAUUAUGGAAUCUGAGAUCGUUUUCAGAGUGGGCCAUCAGAAAGAACUUAGCUUUAUACUGUCAAAAAAAGGCUAAGAUGGUCGAGUCAUUUUCAUUGUGUAGUGUACUUGCACGUUUAUUUUUAGGACAAACACAUUUGAACUUUAUGAAUUUUUUUUUUUUUUUUGCAUGUGAAAUCUUAUGAAUGGCUUUCAUUUUAUACACUAGAAUCUGCCUCAUUUACUCUUAACAUAUGUUUAAGUAUACUGGUAUUAAAACAUUCAAGAAAAGGAUAUUGAUCUAAAAUGCUACCUGAGAUGCAUAAACAUGUCAUCAAGUAGAGAAAAUAUUUUUAUUUUUGCCCAAUAUUUUUUAGACAGUUUGAUUAUUCUUAAAAAUUGAAAACAUAAGCUAAAGAGAUGACUAAAUGGUAGAUUAUUUUGUGUGUGCAUGCUAGGAAAAAUGCUGUUGCUUUAGUUUUGAGCUCUUCAAUGAGUCUAAUUGUGGUAAGGAACAAUAUAAAAUCAGUUUAAAGAUCUUUAAAGGUAGAAUUUUAAAUAGGCAUGAAAUAUAGUGAGAACUUUUAGUAAACAUACUACUUACUCUAAAAUCAAACAUUUUAUUUUCCUAAAGAAUAUAGGUUGCCAAAAAAUAUUUUAUCUCUAAAUAUAGGUUAGCUGUAAUUAUUUCAUGAAUUUUUUUUUUUUUCAAUGUAACUUUUUUUGGUGAAGAUUCAUGGUUCCUAAGUUCUGUAUUCAAGUUUUUGGAAAUGUUUAUUUAAAAACUGUUCUAUACAAGUGUUCAAAACAUUGUAUCUAAAGAGAGUAGCCUGGACUUAAAAUAUUUGAAAUCAGCUUAUGCGUGCCUUUUAAUUUUUUUUUUAAGUUUCUUACUGCCACAUAUGGUGUGAAGUGACAGUAAGUUGCUUAAUGACAUCCUGCAGUAUCUGCUUGCUUUUGGAGACUCCAGUGAGAUGUUGAAAUUGUUCCUGUGCUUGGUAACUACUUUCCUCUGCCAGGCUAUGGGAAAGAGGAUGUAAUUGUGAAUAAUAUACACCAUCCAGUCUUUAAUGUGCUGCAACAAUGUAGUAAUUUGUUUUUUUCAUUUGUUCCCACUGCCUUUGUGUACAUAGAAAACUUAAAAAUUUCCCCCAGUCUAUUAGAAGUUAAGAUGUUCCCUAAUUUAUUAAAUAUGCCUUUAUUCACAAUUUGUUUUUUUAGGUUAUUCUUAAUGCAUUAUAGAAUUAAGUAUGACUUUGUUUAUUUUUAUUACAGUAUGUAGUUAUUGACAUAUUGUGGUUUGCAGAAUUAUCAAUUGUAUAAACUAAACCUUUAAAUUA